AAGGCAACUGGCGGAGUGGCGGCUCCACCAGAGCCUGGGAGCUGCCCCCGCCCCCGAGCCGCGAGCCCCGCGCCGGGCCGGGGAGUCCCCGGCGCCACACGCCCCCACCACCCCCAUCUUAGCGCCCCCCACCCUCUAUGGAGACAUUUCAACCAGGGAGAAGGGAAGUCCUGCCCUUGCCCCUCGCCCCCGCCCUGCUCCUCCAACAGGGGAGACUUCUGUCCAAACCUUGGAAAGAAACGAGAUGCCAGGCCUAGCGCCUUCGGGGAUCCUCUCUGGACAAGGCCACAGGGUGAAAACACCAGCACAGUCUGGACCUGGGCGGACUUUUUGGAAAAGCUUCUGGAUGCCACGGACUCCACGACCAACCAACUAGGUUGCUGCUGCUUGCAAACAUCGCCUCCAUUGAAGGAUUCCUGCAGCCACCAGCUCUGGAACUUUCUGGAACCAAACAUUUCCCCAGACUGCCUACAAGGACCAAUUGGCCUCUGGAUCACUUCCUGGAGGCGUUUGACCGGGACCUGGGAGGGCAGCUGAGAAGUGCCUGACCAUUCUCAAGGAGCUGCGUGGAUUCCAGACAUCUCUGGGCUGGUCUCUGGACCGGGAUGGGGGACCCAGAGGUGGAGCCGAACACACAAGCAGCACUUGAGGGCUCCGAGGGUGGCAAGGAGAGAAGUUCCUGCUCUGGUACAGCCCUGGGACCUUGAAAGGUGCUUCAACAGAGCGUCCACUCCCAGCGCCUAGCUCUGGGACCUUGAAUGGUGCUUUAACAGAGCGUCUGCUCCCAGCGCCAAGCCCUCAGUGCAGAGGGGGAGACUCAGGCGGCCCUCAGACACAAUUCGCCAAGGUCGCACAGCAAGUCAGGGUGCCGCUAAGACUAGGACCUACAGCUCUGCCUCCUGGCCCAGGCUCCUCAGCACCUGGGCCCCAGAGGACAGCCUGUGGGAGGCCCACAUGGCCACUGCACCAUGAACCAAGGACCUGGUCCGGGUCCACCUCCACCAAGUGCUGGCCGUGUGUCACUGGGGUCACUCCACUCUCUGCAUUAGGUCUCAGUCAUCCAAGACCAUCUUUCAAGGGCCGUCACUCCAAUUAUGAGUCUGGGAUUUUCUGAAAUUGAGCAUUUUGGCCAGGCUGUGGGGUCCCUCUAUGACUGCCUGUAAGACACUGCCAAGGGGACUUUCUUCCUUUCACCAGACUGAAGCUAAGAAGUGCUGGAGACAGCAGUUGCUUUAGCCACAGGCUGUGUAGACCACCUGAGGAUGACCUGGGGGUCUGUUUUGUGCACCUUGGAACCCAUCGGAUCCCUCCAAUGGAGCUAUAUAAGGCGGCGUGAGGCAGGCGAGGGGGGCAGCGCAGCCGAGCGGAGCCCAGGAGAGCAGAGAGCGAGCCUGAGCGAGAGACGGGGAAGCACGGAGGAGGAAGCCGCCGGUGCGUCGGGACGGGAGCGCAGGUGCUCGGGCACCCGAGCUGGAGCUCCGCAGCCGCCGGUCAUGUACCGCUCCACCAAGGGCGCCUCCAAGGCGCGCCGGGACCAGAUCAACGCCGAGAUCCGGAACCUCAAGGAGCUGCUGCCGCUGGCCGAAGCGGACAAGGUCCGGCUGUCCUACCUGCACAUCAUGAGCCUCGCCUGCAUCUACACUCGCAAGGGCGUCUUCUUCGCUGGUGGCACUCCUCUGGCGGGCCCCACGGGGCUUCUCUCAGCUCAAGAGCUUGAGGACAUCGUAGCGGCACUACCCGGCUUUCUGCUUGUGUUCACAGCCGAGGGGAAAUUGCUCUACCUGUCUGAGAGUGUGAGCGAGCAUCUGGGCCACUCCAUGGUGGACCUGGUUGCCCAGGGUGACAGCAUCUACGACAUCAUUGACCCAGCUGACCACCUCACUGUGCGCCAGCAACUCACCCUGCCCUCUGCCCUGGACACUGAUCGCCUCUUCCGCUGCCGCUUCAACACCUCCAAGUCCCUCAGGCGCCAGAGUGCAGGCAACAAACUCGUGCUUAUUCGAGGCCGAUUCCAUGCUCACCCACCUGGAGCCUACUGGGCAGGAAAUCCCGUGUUCACAGCUUUCUGUGCCCCUCUGGAGCCGAGACCCCGCCCAGGUCCUGGCCCUGGCCCUGGCCCUGCCUCGCUCUUCCUGGCCAUGUUCCAGAGCCGCCAUGCUAAAGACCUGGCUCUACUGGACAUCUCCGAGAGUGUCCUAAUCUACCUGGGCUUUGAGCGCAGUGAACUGCUUUGUAAAUCAUGGUAUGGACUGCUGCACCCCGAGGACCUGGCCCACGCUUCUGCUCAACACUACCGCCUGUUGGCUGAGAGUGGAGAUAUUCAGGCAGAGAUGGUGGUGAGGCUACAGGCCAAGACUGGAGGCUGGGCAUGGAUUUACUGCCUGUUAUACUCAGAAGGUCCAGAGGGACCCAUUACUGCCAAUAACUACCCAAUCAGUGACAUGGAAGCCUGGAGCCUCCGCCAGCAGUUGAACUCUGAAGACACCCAGGCAGCUUAUGUCCUGGGCACUCCGACCAUGCUGCCCUCAUUCCCUGAAAACAUUCUUUCCCAGGAAGAGUGCUCCAGCACUAACCCACUCUUCACCGCAGCACUGGGGGCUCCCAGAAGCACCAGCUUCCCCAGUGCUCCUGAACUGAGUGUUGUCUCUGCAUCAGAAGAGCUUCCCCGACCCUCCAAAGAACUGGACUUCAGUUACCUGACAUUCCCUUCUGGGCCUGAGCCUUCUCUCCAAGCAGAACUAAGCAAGGAUCUUGUGUGCACUCCACCUUACACGCCCCAUCAGCCAGGAGGCUGUGCCUUCCUCUUCAGCCUCCAUGAGCCCUUCCAGACCCAUUUGCCCACCCCAUCCAGCACUCUUCAAGAACAGCUGACUCCAAGCACUGCGACCUUCUCUGAUCAGUUGACGCCCAGCAGUGCAACCUUCCCAGAUCCACUAACUAGCCCACUGCAAGGCCAGUUGACUGAAACCUCGGUCAGAAGCUAUGAAGACCAGUUGACUCCCUGCACCUCCACCUUCCCAGACCAGCUGCUUCCCAGCACAGCCACCUUCCCAGAGCCUCUGGGCAGCCCUGCCCAUGAACAGCUGACUCCUCCCAGCACAGCAUUCCAAGCACACCUGGACAGCCCCAGCCAAACCUUCCCAGAGCAACUGAGCCCCAACCCUACCAAGACUUACUUUGCCCAGGAGGGAUGCAGUUUUCUCUAUGAGAAGUUGCCCCCAAGUCCUAGCAGCCCUGGUAAUGGGGACUGCACGCUCUUGGCCCUAGCCCAGCUCCGGGGCCCCCUCUCUGUGGAUGUCCCCCUGGUGCCCGAAGGCCUGCUCACACCUGAGGCCUCUCCAGUCAAGCAGAGUUUCUUCCACUACUCUGAAAAGGAGCAGAAUGAGAUAGACCGUCUCAUCCAGCAGAUUAGCCAAUUGGCUCAGGGCAUGGACAGACCCUUCUCAGCUGAGGCUGGCACUGGCGGACUAGAGCCACUUGGAGGACUGGAGCCCCUGGACUCCAACCUGUCCCUGUCAGGGGCAGGCCCCCCUGUGCUCAGCCUGGACCUGAAACCCUGGAAAUGCCAGGAGCUGGACUUCCUGGCUGACCCUGAUAACAUGUUCCUGGAAGAGACGCCCGUGGAAGACAUCUUCAUGGAUCUCUCUACCCCAGAUCCCAGUGAGGAAUGGGGCUCAGGGGAUCCUGAGGCAGAGGGCCCAGGAGGGGCCCCAUCGCCUUGCAACAACCUGUCCCCAGAAGACCACAGCUUCCUGGAGGACCUGGCCACAUAUGAAACCGCCUUUGAGACAGGUGUCUCAGCAUUCCCCUAUGAUGGGUUUACUGAUGAGUUGCAUCAACUCCAGAGCCAAGUUCAAGACAGCUUCCAUGAAGAUGGAAGUGGAGGGGAACCAACGUUUUGAAUAAGUCUGUGACUUAACGUCGUCAAGUAUGGCAUAUUGUCAUCAAGACGUGGAGCCGCUCUCCACCCCCCCGGGACUGUUGGGGGGAUUCUGAGGGCCAGAGGGGGAUAUAUAUGAUUCCCCAGGCCCUGCAGGAUUUUGGGGGGGGGGAGGUGGGAGGGCAAGGGAGGGGAGCUUCUUUUUAAAAUCAAGAGACUUCGAGCGAUCCCAGUUUCCAUUUCAAUCUGUAUUCACUCGUAGUGAGUUUCCUUGAAUGGGAUUUCAAGCGGAGAAUGGGGGAGUCUCACUUCCCCGCCGCCUUGCCCCAUUGGCCUGGGCCAGUUCUCCACUCCUAGGGGCCAAGCCACCCCUAGCCUUGGUGGGGGAAAGGCAGGGCCCACCCGGGCCAGCCCGUGCCCUGAGGGGCUCUUGACACCCACGUAGAAUUCUCUACACACCAGUAACGGGAUUUCAAUUCCGAUGGACUCUGCCGCCCUGGCGGCCCUUCCUGUGACUUUUGCGCCCCGCGCCUGGGGUGGGGGGUGCGAAGAGACGCUACGUUCCUUUCCGAUGGAGGAAGGCAGACCUGCCGUCACACGUGUGCUUGCACGAGUGCGUGUACCUGGUGCGGGACUCACCCGGCCGCCAGACUGCCUGGGCCUGCCCAGAUGGCCACCUCGUGGUGCUGCGGUGACUUUGUAGCCAACUUUAUAAUAAAGUCCAGUUUGCCUUUUUGGUA